GGGAGCUUUUGGGCAGCAGUGAGCUUGCUAGGAAGCGGCGGGGCUGGUGGUGGUGGUAGCAGCGGCGGCAGCGGCGGCAGAGGCGGCGGCGGCGGCGGCGGCGGCGGCGGCGGUGGCGGUGGCGGUGGCGGUGGCAGAUCGGGGGGCGGGGGGGCGGCGGGCGCGUGUCUGUUUGUGAGAUCAAUACUGAGGCCGCGUCCGACCCCCUUGAGCCGAGAUCCCCCCCCAGCCCAGCCCCCACCCCACCCCCCGCACACGCCCCACCCCCCCCACGACCCAGCCUCAUACCGCACCAGCUGAGGCACCCAAGAGGAUUACCCCCUGGGGCCCUCUCCCGCCCCCCAAAAAAGAGAAGAUCCCCUCUCCUGGCCCAUCCCUUCCCUUCUUCCCUCCCCCCUCCCCCCGAACUUUCCCUCUCGCAUGCUUUUCCCCUGCACCACGGAUCGCCUCUCGGAUGCCGCUUGCCUGGAAGCUGCGUUAGGAGCGAGCGGCGGCGGUGGCGGCGGUGGCGGCGGCGGCGGCAGCUCGGGAGUGCUAUGACCGGCAAACUCGCCGAGAAGCUGCCGGUGACCAUGAGCAGUUUGCUAAACCAACUGCCUGACAAUCUGUACCCCGAGGAGAUCCCCAGCGCGCUCAACCUCUUCUCCGGCAGCAGCGACUCGGUAGUCCAUUACAAUCAGAUGGCUACAGAGAAUGUAAUGGACAUCGGUCUGACCAACGAGAAGCCCAACCCGGAACUCUCUUACUCCGGCUCCUUCCAGCCAGCCCCCGGCAACAAGACCGUGACCUACUUGGGAAAGUUCGCCUUCGACUCCCCUUCCAACUGGUGCCAGGACAACAUCAUUAGCCUCAUGAGCGCCGGCAUCUUGGGGGUGCCCCCGGCUUCAGGGGCGCUCAGCACGCAGACGUCCACGGCCAGCAUGGUGCAGCCACCGCAGGGUGACGUGGAGGCCAUGUAUCCCGCGCUACCCCCCUACUCCAACUGCGGCGACCUCUACUCAGAGCCCGUGUCUUUCCACGACCCCCAGGGCAAUCCCGGGCUCGCCUAUUCCCCCCAGGAUUACCAAUCGGCCAAGCCGGCGUUGGACAGCAAUCUCUUCCCCAUGAUUCCUGACUACAACCUCUACCACCACCCCAACGACAUGGGCUCCAUUCCGGAGCACAAGCCCUUCCAGGGCAUGGACCCCAUCCGGGUCAACCCGCCCCCUAUUACCCCUCUGGAGACCAUCAAGGCAUUCAAAGACAAGCAGAUCCACCCGGGCUUUGGCAGCCUGCCCCAGCCGCCGCUCACCCUCAAGCCCAUCCGGCCCCGCAAGUACCCCAACCGGCCUAGCAAGACACCGCUCCACGAACGGCCCCACGCGUGCCCGGCCGAGGGCUGCGACCGCCGUUUCAGCCGUUCGGACGAGCUGACCCGGCACCUGCGCAUCCACACGGGCCACAAGCCCUUCCAGUGCCGGAUCUGCAUGCGGAGCUUCAGCCGCAGCGACCACCUCACCACUCACAUCCGCACUCAUACGGGCGAGAAGCCCUUUGCCUGCGAGUUCUGCGGGCGCAAGUUUGCGCGCAGCGACGAGCGCAAGCGCCACGCCAAGAUCCACCUCAAGCAAAAGGAGAAGAAGGCGGAGAAGGGCGGUGCACCCUCUGCAUCCUCGGCGCCCCCCGUGUCGCUGGCCCCCGUGGUCACCACCUGCGCCUGAGGAUCGGGCCCCCAGAUCCCCACUUUUCCCCUCCAGUGCCUCCCGGCUGCUAGCCUGAAAGCAGCGGGAAAGCCAGCCACGGAGGCGUAGGGGCCGCGCCCUGGCCUCUCCAUGGACGUGCGGCCCCUUGCUUCCCCUUCGAUGCCCCCGGUUCCCAACCUUUCACGCCGGCCAGCGGUCAGGGGCCAGGGCUGGAGGCGCCUUCCCCUCGCGGUCCCCCACUUAGCCAAGGCGUGGGGGCGGAAAGGUGGCGUCUAGCCCGCUUUGUUCAGUUCGGAUCGCCUUGAUCCAGGGGCCGCCGGGCCGCGCCAAGGACCUGCAAGGGACUGAAGGCGGAGCCCAUCCAACCCUCGCCCGACCCAAACACCUCAUUGUUUCCCCCACGUCUCCCUCUAUACCCCCUCGAAGACUCGAGAGGGGGAGGGGGUAAGGAGCGCACCAAAGCGCAGAGCUUGCUGCCCGCCGCACGCACGCGCGCCUGCGUGCGGGGAUGCGCGCGAGUGUGUGCGUGCUCGCGUGUGUGUGUAUGUGUGUGUGUGAGUGUGUGUGUGUGCGCGCGCGCAAGCGUGUGUGUUUAAGACUCUUGAGCUGAACUGGGCUGUGUUUACCCCAAACUCUUCCCCACCUCGGGUCCCCAAGCCGCUGGGAGAUGUCCCAUGCUGGGGGUCCGCACGUGGCUGGAGGAGGUGGUCUUCCAUCCGCUCUGAAAUCAUGUUUCUUAGAGAAAUGCCUCGGAUGCCGCCGACGCGGUGCUGCUGCCGCCGCUUCGGGUUUGGCCCCUCAGAACCCCUCCUUUUCUGAGCGCUUCCCUCUUAGGCCUCAGGGCAGUUUGAUCUGUGGGGAGAAAGAGCAGCCAUCGCUGAGCCUGCCUUUUAAAAUAUAUGUGUAUUUCCUUAGCCCCACUCUAAGAAAUCUAUGUUCCUGAGUUUGCCCCCUGCCCUCCCACUCCUUCCCCUUCUCCCCUCUAAACCUUCUCCCAUCUCUUUCAAAAUCUUUUCCCAGAAAGGCAGGCUUCAACCAGCCACUCCAGCUUUGUGUCUUCUCUCAAUUACAUAGCAAUUUCUCCUUCCCACCAUCAUGGGGAAGCUGGCUCUGCUUUUGCCCUUUGUCAUCACCAACACAACAGAUAGAAUUUAAAUAUAAGUAUAUGGUGUGCGUGUGUAUGUAUGUGUAUGUAUAUGCAUGCAUGUGUAUAAAGAUGCACAUGCGUACAUAUACAUAACAUACACACAAUAUGUAUUCCUAGCAAAAUAAAAUCUCUAAGGUACUUGGUUAUCCAGUGCAGUGCACCGGAAUAAAGAGAAUUUGUAGGCGUAUACAGCUUUAAAUGAUUUAUUUUUUAUGAAAAUGUUAACUGAUGAGAUUAUAUCUACAUACGUGUGUUAUGUGUGUGGAUAUAGAUGCACACAUAUCUGUACAUAUACAUGUGAGUGUACAUAUAUACACAUAUACACAUCUAUGUAUGGAUAUGUGUGUAUACACAUAUACACAUCUCUGUCCAAAAUUUCCUCAAAGAUAUGGGGAUUUUUUCAUGAAUCCAUGUGGAUGAAUGAGGUGUCUCCUUUCCAUACCCAGUCUCACCUUCUCCCCACCCUACCUCACCUCUUCUCAGGCACCCCUCUUCCCCAGCUGUCCUGCCAGCCCUUCUCGUACAGGGUGGCUCCUUUGAAGUGGAGUAAUAGGGAAGGUUGCUCUCUGCCACAGCUUGCAGCAUGGUCUUGACUGAAUGUACUGUUCCUGUUAGCGUUACUUCUCCUGUGGUCAGUAAGUUGCCCAGAGAGAAGGAACAAAGGUCUGGAGUUUACAGAAUGUCUGUUUUUAAAGUCACUUUAUGCGUUUUCCACUUUUUUCUUUUUUAAGAAAAAGAAGUACCAUUUUUGUUUUGUUUUGUUUUGAUUUUUGGUGGUGGAUAAAUAAUACUAAAAGGACUCUAGUGGAAAGGGGGGAUAUCGAAGAGCAGGGGGUUGUGAAUUUCCAGGUACUUGGACUUUUUGUAGAAGGAGAGAGAAGAAGAUGAAGUUUGCCAGGAGGGCCCAUAUUUUUUCAGCUGAAGGGUAAAAUCUUUCUUUGCAGAGACAGUAUUUUGCUGAAUACUUUUUAUAAUGUGAUGAUUAUUAAAAAAGCAAAAAUUUUGGUCACUUCCAAGCUAGAAGGAGGAAUCAGAUACCCUUUAAUAUUUUUUCCUCGCUCCUUCUGGUAUAUGCAUGUCACUGCAUGAUAAUUGAGUUUUCCUUUGUUUUAAUAAAACUGUUCUCAGACAUUAAGCUAAACUAAGAGAAAAAUAACUUUGUUGCCAAAAGGUUGUGCUAUCCAGAUUUUUUAUAUGUCUGCAUGUUUAAAAAAAAAAAGCAACAAAAGAAAAUGCACUCUAACUUAUGUGAACUGAGAGAAAAAAAUCAGGUUUUAAACAGGAAAACCUAUGGGGAAUGAUAUUUUUUGAAAGACUUUUGUAUAAAGUUGAGUACUUAGAAAAAAGACAAACCAGAUGUAAUAUAUUUUGUGGAUGUUUUUAUUUCUUGGAUUUAUAGUACCUUAUACUAAGGUUAAAAAAAUAUGCUUGAUAUUGUGAAAAGGUGAAAUUCUUCACCAACAUUUCAUUUGCUCCUUUGUCAUAUUGUAAUGCCAAUAUAAUAUAGUUAAUGAAAACAGCAUUUUUAAAAACCGAAAUAUUGAAAUGGUGUAAUGUUGUACCAUUUGCACUGUGAGCAAAUGCUAAUACAGUAAAUAUAUUGUGUUUGCUGACAAUCAGCCGGCCUAUAAAUCUCCUUAUUUUAUUUCUUGUUUUUAUAGCAUAAAGCUUUAGUUUGGCCUGUU